AGUGACCGGCGACGCGGGCAAGAUGGCGGCGCUGGGGGUGGCGGAGGCCGUGGCGGCCCCACACCCGGCUGAGGGGGCCGAGACGGCUGAGGCGGUGGAGCUGAGCCGCGCCCUGAGCCGCCUGCUGCCGGGGCUGGAGGCCGACAGCAAGCCGGGCCGGCGGCGCGCCUUGGAGGCCCUGCGGCGCGCGCUGGAGGAGCCAGGCCCUGCCGCCGACCCCACCGCUUUCCAGGGCCCCUGGGCGCGCCUACUGCUGCCGCGCUUGCUGCGCUGCCUGAGCGACCCCGCCGAGGGCUGCCGCGCGCUGGCAGUGCACCUGCUGGAUCUGGGCCUGCGCCGCGCCGCGCGGCCCCGCGAUGCCCUGCCGCGCCUGCUGCCCGCGCUCGCCGCGCGCUUGGCCGGCCCCGUGCCCGCGCGCCGCCCGCCCGAGGCCUGUGAGGAGCUGCGCCUGGCGCUUGUGCAGCUGCUGGGCCUGGCCGUGGACCUGUGCGGCGCCGCGCUCGCGCCCCACCUGGACGACGCUCUGCGCGCGCUGCGCUGCUCCCUGCUCGACCCCUUCGCCGCCGUGCGCCGCGAGAGCUGCAGCUGCGCCGCCGCCCUGGCGCAGGCCACGCCCGACCACUUCCACAUGCAGUCGGAGUCUCUGAUCGGGCCCCUGAUGCAGACCAUCUCCCACCAGCACUGGAAGGUCCGUGUGGCCGCCAUUGAAGCCACAGGCGCAGUGAUCCAUUUUGGCAACGGGAAGUCCGUGGACGACGUGCUUUCCCAUUUUGCUCAGCGACUGUUUGAUGACGUCCCGCAGGUCCGGCGGGCGGUGGCCUCCGUGGUGGGCGGCUGGCUGCUGUGUCUGCGUGACCGUUACUCCUUCUUCCACAAGCUCAUCCCUCUGCUGCUCAGUAGCCUCAACGACGAGGUGCCUGAGGUCAGGCAGCUGGCUGCCAGCCUCUGGGAGGACGUUGGCCUGCAGUGGCAGAAGGAGAAUGAGGAGGACCUGAAGGACAAGCUGGACUUUGCCCCUCCCACCCCACCCCAUUACCCUCCACAUGAGCGCCGCCCUGUGCUGGGCUGCCGGGAGCUCGUCUUCAGGAACCUCUCCAAGAUCCUCCCUGCCCUGUGCCACGACAUCACCGACUGGGUGGUGGGGACCCGAGUGAAGUCGGCACAGCUGCUCCCAGUGCUGCUGCUGCAUGCCGAGGACCACGCCACGCAGCACCUGGAGGUCGUCCUCCGGACCCUGUUCCAGGCCUGCACCGACGAGGAGGCAGCCGUGGUCCAAAGUUGUACCAGAUCCGCAGAGCUCGUCGGGACGUUUGUCAGCCCUGAGGUGUUUCUGAAGCUGAUCUUAUCGACGCUGAAGAAGACGCCCUCUGCCUCCGGCCUCCUGGUGCUGGCCUCCGCCAUGCGGGGUUGCCCCCGAGAAGCCCUCCAGCCGCACCUGGCAGCCAUCGCCACAGAGCUGGCACAGGCCCACAUCUGCCAGGCAUCUGAAAACGACCUCUACCUGGAGCGCCUGCUGCUGUGUGUGCAGGCUCUGGUGUCUGUGUGUCAUGAGGACUGUGGCGUGGCCAGCCUGCAGCUCUUGGACGUGCUGCUGACAAUAGUGGCCCUCGCAGGUGCUACCGGCCUGAGGGACAAGGCACAGGAGACGAUGGACUCACUGGCCAUGGUGGAGGGUGUCAGCAGCUGCCAGGACCUCUACCGCAAGCACAUUGGUCCCCUCCUGGAGCGGGUGACCGCGUCGCACCUUGACUGGACCGCACACUCGCCGGAGCUCCUGCAGUUCAGUGUCAUCGUCGCACAGUCAGGCCCUGCCCUGGGAGAAGCCCUGCCACACGUCGUGCCCACGCUGAGGGCCUGUCUGCAGCCCUCCCAAGACCCGCAGAUGCGCCUGAAGCUGUUCUCCAUCCUGUCCACCGUGCUGCUCAGAGCCACGGACACCAUCAACUCCCAGGGGCAGUUUCCCAGCUACCUCGAGACGGUGACAAAGGACAUCCUGGCCCCCAAUCUGCAGUGGCAUGCGGGGAGGACAGCCGCGGCCAUCCGCACGGCUGCCGUGUCCUGCCUCUGGGCGCUCACCAGCAGCGAGGUCCUGUCGGCAGAGCAGAUACGGGACGUGCAGGAAACACUGAUGCCCCAGGUCCUGACCACCCUGGAGGAGGAUUCGAAGAUGACGCGACUGAUCUCAUGCCGUAUUAUCAACACGUUCUUAAAAACCUCGGGCGGCAUGACGGAUCCAGAGAAACUCAUCAGGAUUUAUCCUGAACUCUUAAAACGCCUAGAUGACGUGUCCAACGAUGUGAGGAUGGCAGCCGCCUCCACCUUGGUCACCUGGCUGCAGUGUGUCAAGGGUGCCAACGCAAAAUCCUACUAUCAGAGCAGUGUCCAGUACCUGUACCGAGAGUUGCUGGUUCACCUUGACGAUCCAGAGAGGGCCAUCCAGGAUGCAAUUUUAGAGGUCCUCAAAGAGGGCAGCGGGCUGUUCCCAGAUCUCCUGGUGAGGGAGACGGAGGCCGUCAUCCACAAGCACCGCUCGGCCACCUACUGCGAGCAGCUCCUGCAGCAUGUGCAGGCCGUGCCAGCCACACAGUGACCACGCUGGUUUCAGCCACGGCACACCCUUGUCCCCACCUGAGCCAGAGUUUGUGGCCUUUAAAUCUCAUAAACAAGGCACCUCUGUGCCAGCAGUGAGACUGUGACAGCAAGAAUGUACUCCUCAGGACACCUGCCCACUCUUUCCCUGGAAUAACAGCCUCUGAGUGGAUUCUGCAUGUUAUGUGAUUUGUUCUGUUCAUCGAGAGGGCUCCCAAACAUCUGCAGCUGAUUUGAAAUUAAAAGUAAGUCGCAGCCGCUCCUCCCGCAGCCACUUCAGCAGCAUCUUAGAUUUUAAGCCUCACGUGCGCAGCUGGUUCAUGAACUAUUGGCUGCAUCCUGCUUAGGUGCCCACCAAGAAGGUUUUUACCUACUUAACAAAAAAGAAAGAAGCCAAAGUGAUUAGAAAGAAAUGAAAUCUCUUUUUGGGUUCUGUCUACUGAAAUUUAAUAUCUCAGUGAACAGACUAAAAGGAAUUUAGAAUCCUAACAACUUAUCAGAUUUCUCCUGUUUUAAAUAUACUGGGACUUUAAAGGUUAUAUGUCCGGUCACCGUAUGUUUUAAGUCGGUGUUAAUGCUAACAGUGUUGAAAACAAUAUUUCAUGAGAUCUAAUUGUGGUUGCCCCUAUAGGUAGCAGGAAAGUAAAGUUGCAUUUCCCUCUCGCACAUUCUACACCCAAGUGCCUAAAAGAUCUCAUUGUAAGUGGGUAGUGUUACCGGAAGCCAUUGUGUUCACACGGGGGAAAUGCCGUAUAUAUUUUUCAACAAAUAUUAACGUUUAUACUUUCAUGUUUGAAAAUUUAAUUAAAAAUGUUUGUUUUAA